ACACGUGUGAGCCUAGAGGCGGGUCCCGGUUGCAGACUUGCCAUGGCCUCCGAAGCUUCUGUGCGUCUAGGGGUGCCCCCUGGCCGUCUGUGGAUCCAGAGGCCUGGCAUCUACGAAGAUGAGGAGGGGAGAACCUGGGUGACUGUGGUCGUGCGGUUCAAUCCCUCGCGUAGGGAAUGGGCCAGGGCCUCCCAGGGCAGCAGAUAUGAACCCAGCAUCACAGUGCACUUGUGGCAGAUGGCAGUGCAUACCCGGGAGCUACUCUCCUCCGGCCAGAUGCCCUUCUCCCAGCUGCCCGCCGUGUGGCAGCUCUACCCCGGGAGGAAGUACCGAGCAGCGGAUUCCAGUUUCUGGGAAAUAGCAGACCAUGGCCAGAUUGACUCUAUGGAGCAGCUGGUCCUAACAUAUCAGCCGGAGAGGAAAGACUGACACUGGGAGUGGCUGGCCCUGCUGGCCCUGCCUCUUCUGGCCUGGUGUCUCCUCAUGCCCCCUCAGUGAGGAUCUUCAUGUACCUGCUCUUCUGUUUGCACACCCAGCAUAGCCUCCUUGCAGGCAGAAGGCAGUAGGGCCCCUGCACACUCAGUUUCUCUCGUUUUCCUUAGUUAUCAGUCCUGUCCUGUCCCACUCAGGUCUGUACUUAGGGCAGCUGGCCUGGAUGGGCUUCACUGGGGCCCUGUCUGUGUGCUGAGCCAGUUUCCCCUGCUGGCUGCAAGCUGUGGGUUCUUUCUCCUCUGUGCCCCUCAUGCUGAUCUUCUAGAUGCCACUCCCAAAUCCCCUUCAUACCCACCAGGAUGUGUGCCCAGCCAGGCCUCCAGCACCCCCAGUGCAGCUCGUGAUUGGAAACUCACCAUCGGCAGGCAGUGGUUCGGUUUAAGAGAUGGCAUUAGAGGGAGCCCAGUCUGGAUGUGGACUUGGAUGCCCUGUGGGUAUCAGUUCUGCUGACACUUUGGCCCGAAAUAGAUCCAGUGCUGAGCAAGCAAUGUACACCAGAGCCUCAGUGAGCCCAUCUGCACAGUGGGGAGCAUGGAGGGAUGGGUUUGGCCUGUGCUUCUGCUUAUUCAGUCCUUCAGCUCACGGAAGGGAUGCUAGUCCGUGAAGGUGACCUCACAGUACUGGUUAAUUAAACUUUAUUGCUCACUGUC